CAUCUAUUUGUUUAUUUACAGAAUAAUUACCUUUAUCUCACCCUGCCCUCACUUGCUCCCUCCACUUCUAGCAAGUAAGCAGGGAGCCUGGCUAUCUUGCUGCCAUCACUGUGUUCUCCAGCACCUGGCUUGGUGCCUGGCACAGAGGUGUUGCUCUGUAUUUUCGGAUGAAUGAAUGCAUAGGAACUAGAGAAGCCUAGAUGGAUCCGGCUCUGCCUUACUCGCGGAGUUUGGGCAAGCCUGUUUCCUGCUGCGUGAAGUAGGGGGUGGAGGAAGCGGGGUGUUAAGCUACAAGGUGUUGAUUAGCUGUAAGAUUUCAGCCUUGUUUUCUCCGUAGUCUUCGGGCUGGAGCCAGCCACUUGACGUCCGGCGCCUCAGCUCCCCACCUGUAUAAUGGGUGUGAACUCAUCCCGAGGUCUAGGGGUGGUAGCGCUGCCUUAUAAGGCGGCAGAGGCCGAGGGAAGGCGAGGCCGAGUGGGUGGAGAGAAAUCACAACAUCCGGCUGCGGGGGCUGGGCGGGGCGCCUGCGGCGACCGGGCAAGAGGUCGGGGAACGGCUGCGAGGCCGCAGCCUCCUCCCUGUCUCUCCCUCUUUCGAUGUGCGCCCUCCUGAUUGGGGCCGACCCAAGGGAAUACGGCCACACAAGUGGACCAAACAAACUCGCUGCCAGCCCGCAGGAGGCCCAGGAUACGGAGCGCGUCCCCGACAAAACCCUAGAAAAGCCGUCUGCGAGCCAAAGGCCGCCGGGCCACACCUUCAGGCGACGACCCAAUCAAAAUGCAGUACUUGAGAUGACGGACGUCUUCUUCACCCAAUCACAUAUUCGGCCUCCUGGGCGUGCCCCAGAGUACCCACCUCCAUUGUCCCGGCUGAGGGCUCGGCCCUAAUUGGCAGUUUGGUAUCCUACGAAAGCCUAGAAAUUCGAACCUAGGGGCUGAACCCCGCCCUCAGACCAACCAGGAAGAGGUGACGUGAUUGGUCCCGCCCCCGUACUUCUUUGAGCGAGUCCCCAGCUGGGGGGGCGGGGGAAAAAAUGAAGAGGAAGACUAAUGGGAAGACGGCGCGGGGAGCUUCUGCCCGGUGAUUGGUCAAAUGAGGUGGCGGUGGAAAUCGCAAAGGCAAAAGCAAGAAAUGGCGGCAGAUGCUCCAGUUCCCUCACAUCAGCCAGUGCGAAGAGCUGCGGCUCAGCCUCGGCCGAGUAUGAAGUGACCCCGGAUGACAAGCGGAAGGCAUGUGGGCGGCAGCUAACGCAGAAUUUUCUGAGCCACACGGGUCCUGACCUCAUCCCUGAGGUCCCCCGGCAGCUGGUGACGAACUGCACCCAGCGGCUGGAGCAGGGUCCCUGCAAAGACCUUUUCCAGGAACUCACCCGGCUGACCCACGAGUACCUGAGCGUGGCCCCUUUUGCCGACUACCUCGACAGCAUCUACUUCAACCGUUUCCUGCAGUGGAAGUGGCUGGAAAGGCAGCCAGUGACCAAAAACACCUUCAGGCAAUACCGAGUCCUGGGCAAAGGUGGCUUUGGGGAGGUGUGCGCCUGCCAGGUGCGGGCCACAGGUAAGAUGUAUGCCUGCAAGAAGCUAGAGAAAAAGCGGAUCAAGAAGCGGAAAGGGGAGGCCAUGGCGCUGAACGAGAAGCAGAUCCUGGAGAAAGUGAACAGUAGGUUUGUAGUGAGCUUGGCCUACGCCUAUGAGACCAAGGACGCGCUGUGCCUGGUGCUGACACUGAUGAACGGGGGCGACCUCAAGUUCCACAUCUACCACAUGGGCCAGGCUGGCUUCCCCGAAGCGCGGGCCGUCUUCUACGCCGCCGAGAUCUGCUGUGGCCUGGAGGACCUGCACCGGGAGCGCAUCGUGUACAGGGACCUGAAGCCCGAGAACAUCUUGCUGGAUGACCACGGCCACAUCCGCAUCUCUGACCUGGGACUAGCUGUGCAUGUGCCCGAGGGCCAGACCAUCAAAGGGCGUGUGGGCACCGUGGGUUACAUGGCUCCGGAGGUGGUGAAGAAUGAACGGUACACGUUCAGCCCUGACUGGUGGGCGCUCGGCUGCCUCCUGUACGAGAUGAUCGCAGGCCAGUCGCCCUUCCAGCAGAGGAAGAAGAAGAUCAAGCGGGAGGAGGUGGAGCGGCUGGUGAAGGAGGUCCCCGAGGAGUAUUCCGAGCGCUUUUCCCCGCAGGCCCGCUCACUUUGCUCACAGCUCCUCUGCAAGGACCCUGCCGAACGCCUGGGGUGUCGUGGGGGCAGUGCCCGCGAGGUGAAGGAGCACCCCCUCUUUAAGAAGCUGAACUUCAAGCGGCUGGGAGCUGGCAUGCUGGAGCCGCCGUUCAAGCCUGACCCCCAGGCCAUUUACUGCAAGGAUGUUCUGGACAUUGAACAGUUCUCUACGGUCAAGGGCGUGGAGCUGGAGCCUACCGACCAGGACUUCUACCAGAAGUUUGCCACAGGCAGUGUGCCCAUCCCCUGGCAGAACGAGAUGGUGGAGACCGAGUGCUUCCAAGAGCUGAAUGUCUUUGGGCUGGAUGGCUCAGUUCCCCCAGACCUGGACUGGAAGGGCCAGCCACCUGCACCUCCUAAAAAGGGACUGCUGCAGAGACUCUUCAGUCGCCAAGAUUGCUGUGGAAACUGCAGCGACAGCGAGGAAGAGCUCCCCACCCGCCUCUAGCCCCCAGCCCGAGGCCCCCACCAGCAGUUGGCGGUAGCAGCUACUCCGAGCGCCGUUUACAGUUUUGCACAGUGAUCUUCCCCAUUGUCCACUCAAGUCGUGGCCUGGGGAACACAGACGGAGCUGUCCCCAGUGUCCUCCGUCCCUCAGCCCCUGGCCUGGCUGAGUUUGGCAGGGCCUGGGCCAUCCCUGGGACAAAGGUGCGUCCCUUCAGCUCUUCUCCGUGGAGCUCGGGGCUUUCUGUAUUUAUGUAUUUGUACGAAUGUAUAUAGCGACCAGAGCAUUCUUAAUUCCCGCCGCAGACCUGGCGCCCCCGCCUUGGCUCCUGGGGGCAGCCAGCCCUGGCUGGGAGAGCGGGAGCUGGCAGAGGAGCCACUGCCAAACUCAAGGCUCCUCUGGCCCAGCUUGGAUGGCUGAGGGUGGUCACACCCCUGAGCCUUCAGCACUGUGCUGGCCACCCCGGCCUCUGAGUAAGACUCGUGCCUCCCCCUGCUGCCCUGGGCUCAGGCUGCUACCCUCUGGGGCCCAAAGCUGUCCCUUCUCAGUGCUUGUCAGCGCUGGGUCUGGGGCCUCUGUAUGCCCUAGGCCUGUGCCAAAGUGGCCAGAGAUUGGGCUGCCUGUGAUACCCAUCAGCCCACUGCCCCGGCCGGCCCAGAUAGGUCUGCCUCUGCCUUCCAGCUCCCACAGCCUGGUCCCUGAUACUGGGCUCUGUCCUGCAGACACCUCUUUCAGAAACGCCCAAGCCCAGCCCCUAGGAGGGGGUGGGGCAUCCCUGGUCAACCCUCAAACAUUCCGGACUCCCCUCAUAACAAUAGACACAUGUGCCCAGCAAUAAUCCGCCCCUUCCUGUGUGCGCCUGUGGGGUGCGUGCGCGCGCGUGUGUACCUGUGUGGGUGAAGGGGAUAGGGCGAGGCUGUGCCUGUGCCCCAGGUCCCAGCCCUGGCCCUUCCCAGACUGUGAUGGCCAUCCUGGUCCCAGUGUUAGGGUAGCAUGGGAUUACAGGGCCCUGUUUUUUCCAUAUUUAAAGCCAAUUUUUAUUACUCGUUUUGUCCAACGUAAGCUGCCACAUGUCUCUGUGUGAAUAGUCCGAGCACAAACCUG